GUCCGGUGACGCUGCCAGCGCCCGGAGCACCAGGGGCCGAAGGGGUCCACAGAGCAGCCGCGGGACCCCCGGAAACCCAUUGCGACCGGCCCCAGGAGACCCACCACCAGGCUCCCACUGUGCCGAGCUUCCCGCUCGCCCGGCCCCGCGGGUAGCGAAAGCGACAAUGUUCCCCUGAGGCCACGACAGAGCCGGCGUGCCGAGAUGCCCAAACCCCGCGCGGGGGCCAGCGACUCUCGCGCCAGUAGGCCCUUGACUUGGAUCAAGACGGGGGACGGGGGACUCCCAGGACGCGAGCAGAGUGAACGAGGACAAGGGCCCCGCGGCGAGGGCAUCGGCUCUCGCCGGCGGAUGACGAGCUGUAUCAGCGGACGCGCAUCUCUCUGCUGCAACGCGAGGCCGCUCAGGCAAUGUACAUCGACAGCUACAACAGCCGCGGCUUCAUGAUAAACGGAAACCGCGUGCUCGGCCCCUGCGCUCUGCUCCCGCACUCGGUGGUGCAGUGGAACGUGGGAUCCCACCAGGACAUCACCGAAGACAGCUUUUCCCUCUUCUGGUUGCUGGAGCCCCGGAUAGAGAUCGUGGUGGUGGGGACUGGAGACCGGACCGAGAGGCUGCAGUCCCAGGUGCUUCAAGCCAUGAGGCAGCGGGGCAUUGCUGUGGAAGUGCAGGACACGCCCAAUGCCUGUGCCACCUUCAACUUCCUGUGUCAUGAAGGCCGAGUAACUGGAGCUGCUCUCAUCCCUCCACCAGGAGGGACUUCACUUACAUCUUUGGGCCAAGCUGCUCAAUGAACCGCCAGGAACUGACCUGCUGACUGCACUCUGCCAGGCUUCCCAAUGCUUUCACUCUUAUCUACCCUUUGGCACUUAUCUUGCUUAUCAACAUAAUAAUUUAUACACUUCUCCCAUUUUGUAUCAGGUGUGUUGCUGGCCAGGAGCUGAUGGCUCACUGGGCUCUUGGAGGGGAAUGUGAAGAAACCAAGGAGUCACUUUUUCAUCUAGAUUACUUAGGAUUCCUUGACUUUUCAGAAGUCGGGAAGCAGUAUGUUUGCCUGUUGUAGACCUACUUGCUCACAUGCAGAUUUGAGAGGACCUCAACGGCUUUUCUCACAAAA